AUCUUGUGUUGUUGAGGCUGAGGACUGACUGGGGUUCUGAGACUCCCUGUCCCGGACCGCAGAUUAUAGUGGGACCAGUCUCAUUAGGUUGAAUCUACAGCCUAUGUUGGUGUUAACCCAGGUCUCUUAGAGCGUUAAAAGGAUCUGAACAAAGUCUGCUCAAAUCUCCUGCUGUGAACCAGCAGAAUUUUUGAACAGAGACCACGUCUCCACCUCCUGGGCUCCAACGAUUCUCCCAUCUUGGCCUCCCAAAGCGCUGGAUUUACAGGUUUCUUCACAUAUAAAAAUCUAUUGUAAAAAUACGGAAAAGAAUGGCAGCGGAAACGCAGACACUGAACUUUGGGCCUGAAUGGCUCCGAGCUCUGUCCAGUGGUGGGAGUAUUACAUCCCCUCCUCUUUCUCCAGCAUUGCCGAAGUAUAAAUUAGCAGAUUAUCGUUACGGCAGAGAAGAAAUGUUAGCACUUUUCCUUAAAGACAACAAGAUACCUUCAGACCUUCUGGAUAAAGAAUUUCUGCCUAUCCUCCAGGAGGAACCCCUUCCACCAUUGGCUCUGGUACCCUUUACAGAAGAAGAACAGAGAAACUUUUCCAUGUCUGUAAAUAGUGCUGCUGUCCUGCGAUUGACAGGACGAGGAGGAGGAGGAACAGUGGUGGGGGCUCCUAGAGGUCGAAGUUCUUCAAGAGGGCGAGGCAGAGGCAGAGGUGAAUGUGGUUUCUACCAAAGAAGUUUUGAUGAAGUAGAGGGUGUUUUUGGUCGAGGAGGUGGCAGAGAAAUGCAUAGAUCGCAGAGCUGGGAGGAAAGGGGUGACAGACGUUUUGAAAAACCAGGACGAAAAGAUGUAGGGAGACCAAAUUUUGAGGAAGGUGGACCAACAUCAGUAGGGAGAAAGCAUGAAUUUAUACGCUCAGAAAGUGAAAAUUGGCGCAUCUUUAGAGAGGAACAAAAUGGAGAAGAUGAAGAUGGAGGUUGGCGACUAGCUGGAUCAAGGAGGGAUGGAGAGAGGUGGCGACCUCACAGUCCUGAUGGCCCUCGUUCUGCAGGCUGGCGGGAACACAUGGAACGACGUCGGAGGUUUGAGUUUGAUUUUCGAGAUAGAGAUGAUGAACGGGGUUACCGAAGGGUUCGCUCUGGCAGUGGGAGCAUAGAUGAUGACAGGGAUAGCUUGCCCGAAUGGUGCUUAGAGGAUGCUGAAGAAGAAAUGGGUACAUUUGACUCAUCUGGAGCAUUCCUUUCUCUAAAAAAAGUACAGAAAGAGCCUAUUCCAGAAGAGCAGGAGAUGGACUUCCGGCCUGUGGACGAAGGGGAGGAGUGCUCUGACUCUGAGGGUAGCCAUAAUGAAGAGGCCAAAGAACCCGAUAAGACAAAUAAGAAAGAAGGAGAGAAAACAGAUAGAGUAGGAGUUGAAGCUAGUGAGGAAACUCCCCAGACCUCAUCAUCAUCUGCUAGACCAGGUACUCCUUCAGACCAUCAGUCUCAGGAAGCAUCACAGUUUGAGAGGAAAGAUGAACCAAAAACUGAGCAAACGGAAAAAGCUGAAGAGGAGACUCGGAUGGAAAAUAGUCUACCAGCCAAAGUGCCCAGCAGAGGGGAUGAAAUGGUUGCUGAUGUCCAGCAGCCCCUGUCGCAGAUUCCUUCAGAUACAGCCUCUCCUCUUCUCAUACUUCCACCUCCUGUUCCCAAUCCUAGUCCUACUCUCCGGCCAGUUGAAACACCAGUUGUAGGUGCUCCUGGUAUGGGCAGUGUUUCCACAGAACCUGAUGAUGAAGAAGGUCUCAAACAUUUGGAGCAGCAAGCUGAGAAAAUGGUGGCUUAUCUCCAAGACAGUGCACUAGAUGAUGAAAGAUUGGCAUCAAAACUGCAAGAGCACAGAGCUAAAGGAGUGUCGAUUCCAUUGAUGCAUGAAGCAAUGCAGAAGUGGUAUUACAAAGAUCCUCAGGGAGAAAUUCAAGGUCCCUUCAAUAAUCAGGAGAUGGCAGAAUGGUUUCAGGCGGGCUAUUUUACUAUGUCUUUAUUGGUGAAGAGAGCGUGUGAUGAAAGCUUCCAACCUCUUGGCGAUAUCAUGAAAAUGUGGGGAAGGGUUCCCUUUUCUCCAGGUCCAGCUCCCCCUCCUCAUAUGGGAGAGCUGGACCAGGAACGACUGACCAGGCAGCAAGAACUCACAGCCUUAUACCAGAUGCAGCACCUGCAGUACCAGCAGUUUUUAAUACAACAACAAUAUGCACAGGUUUUGGCCCAACAGCAGAAAGCAGCACUGUCUUCCCAGCAGCAGCAGCAGUUGGCACUUCUUCUUCAACAGUUUCAGACCUUGAAGAUGAGAAUAUCUGAUCAGAACAUCAUUCCCUCAGUAACUAGGUCUGUGUCCGUGCCAGAUACUGGCUCUAUCUGGGAGCUUCAGCCAACAGCUUCACAGCCUACAGUUUGGGAAGGUGGUAGUGUAUGGGAUCUUCCUCUGGACACCACGACACCAGGCCCUGCCCUGGAACAGCUUCAGCAGCUAGAGAAGGCCAAAGCUGCAAAGCUAGAGCAAGAGAGAAGAGAGGCAGAAAUGAGGGCAAAACGGGAAGAGGAAGAGCGAAAGAGGCAGGAAGAACUCCGAAGACAACAGGAGGAAAUUCUUCGGCGACAGCAGGAAGAAGAAAGGAAAAGGCGAGAGGAAGAAGAACUUGCCCGAAGGAAACAGGAAGAGGCUCUGCGUCGCCAGCGGGAGCAAGAAAUUGCAUUAAGGCGACAGCGAGAAGAGGAAGAAAGACAGCAGCAAGAAGAAGCUCUUAGAAGACUGGAAGAGAGGAGAAGAGAAGAGGAAGAAAGGCGGAAGCAGGAAGAAUUGUUACGCAAACAGGAAGAGGAGGCUGCAAAAUGGGCCCGGGAAGAAGAAGAAGCCCAGCGUCGAUUAGAGGAGAACCGGCUGCGGAUGGAAGAGGAGGCAGCCAGACUCCGGCAUGAGGAAGAAGAACGGAAGAGAAAGGAGCUGGAGGUCCAGCGGCAGAAGGAGUUAAUGCGCCAGAGGCAGCAGCAGCAAGAGGCUCUCCGGAGGUUGCAGCAGCAGCAGCAGCAACAACAGCUGGCGCAGAUGAAGCUUCCUUCUUCUUCAACGUGGGGCCAGCAGUCCAAUACAACAGCAUGUCAGUCCCAGGCCACGCUGUCGUUGGCUGAAAUCCAAAAACUAGAGGAAGAACGAGAACGGCAGCUUCGAGAAGAGCAAAGGCGCCAGCAGAGGGAGUUGAUGAAAGCUCUUCAGCAGCAGCAGCAACAGCAACAGCAGAAACUCUCAGGUUGGGGGAAUGUCAGCAAACCUUCAGGUACCACGAAAUCUCUUCUGGAGAUCCAGCAGGAAGAGGCCAGGCAAAUGCAAAAGCAGCAGCAGCAGCAGCAGCAACACCAGCAACCAAACAGAGCUCGUAACAAUACGCAUUCCAACCUGCACACCAGCAUUGGGAAUUCUGUUUGGGGCUCUAUAAAUACUGGUCCUCCUAACCAGUGGGCAUCUGACCUAGUCAGUAGUAUUUGGAGUAAUGCUGACACUAAAAACUCCAACAUGGGAUUCUGGGAUGAUGCAGUGAAAGAGGUGGGACCUAGGAAUUCAACAAAUAAAAAUAAAAACAACGCCAGUCUCAGUAAAUCUGUAGGUGUGUCUAACCGGCAGAAUAAGAAAGUAGAAGAAGAAGAAAAGUUGCUGAAGCUCUUUCAGGGAGUAAAUAAAGCCCAAGAUGGAUUUACGCAGUGGUGUGAACAGAUGCUUCAUGCCCUUAAUACGGCAAAUAACUUGGAUGUUCCCACAUUUGUUUCUUUCCUGAAAGAAGUAGAAUCUCCUUAUGAGGUCCAUGAUUAUAUCAGGGCCUAUUUAGGAGAUACUUCUGAGGCCAAGGAGUUUGCCAAGCAGUUCCUUGAGCGCCGUGCCAAACAGAAAGCCAACCAGCAGCGUCAGCAGCAGCAGCUGCCACAGCAGCAGCAGCAGCAGCCGCCACAGCAGCCGCCACAGCAGCCACAACAGCAGGACUCUGUGUGGGGGAUGAACCACAGUACACUCCAUUCAGUAUUUCAGACCAAUCAAAGCAACAACCAACAAUCCAAUUUUGAGGCUGUGCAGAGUGGCAAGAAGAAGAAAAAGCAGAAGAUGGUCCGAGCAGAUCCCAGUUUAUUAGGAUUUUCAGUCAAUGCAUCAUCGGAGCGACUCAACAUGGGUGAAAUCGAGACGUUGGAUGACUACUGAGCACCUGCCAGUGGACUGGCCAUCCCUCUCCUGUCUGCCGACUAUGGAGUCUCCACCUUUGGACACAACACUUACUCACCAUUUACUCUUUAUCACUCUGCAACAAAUCACAGAACCGAUCAUCUCAGGCUUUUUCUUCUGGCCCUUUGUGUCCAAGAUUCUUUAAUCCAUUUUUGUUGGUGAACAUCUCAGACUAUAGAUAAGUGGACUGGACCCUGUGUCUUGGGGGUGGCAGUUGGGAUUACUCCCCAACAAGGCUGAUUUUAGGCAGCAUGUGUUCACUGUGCUGUGAUUUCAUCUACUGUCUCCCAGAAAGUGUGUUGGGAUCGGCCAUUAGCAGCUUGCUUUCUCUUGUCACUUUUUUUCUUCUAUUUUGUUUUUUCUUCUUCUUUUUCCCCCCAUCAGGGCAAAUGGUCUAACUGGUGCAAUCAUGAAGAGAGUUAAUGGUUAACAGACAUUGGCCAAUAACAAAACACCCCAUGGACUGUGACUCGAGUAUCCAACAGGCAGUCAGAGCUCUCCCGGUCUGAAAGUUGCAUUGCCACUGCUAACUUUGGGAUUGCAUCAGAGAGGCCCUGAGUGGGGUUGAGAUGAGGUUGGUUUGGUUUGAUGUUACACACUCCUCACCUGUUCUUUCUGAGUGUCCUUUCUCUGAAAGGAUUUAUGUUUUUCUUCGUUAGAUAGUGACUUCUGAGCAAGCUGAUCUCCCCUGGCAUGCUCCAACCUGAUUGGACAAAGGAAGCUCUAUGGCCUGGGAGAGAGACUAUUCUUAAUUUUUCUUUCUUACAAAAACUGAUUUUUCCCAUAAAUAUUUUUACUUCAGAGGACUAGGACCAUUUUGUUUUGGGCCCUUCUGCUGAAAAUUUGUCUCGUUUAAGAGGCAGCUAGAAUCUUUACCAUAUGUAUGAAUUUGUAUAAUUUCAUUUUUGGAUAGGGAUAAACUUUUGCUUCUGAUAAAAGCCUGGAAUUUCAUCUGGUCCUCAGAGCAUUGCGUGUGUGUCUUGCUGUAGCCCGGAAAAGGUUUUGUGUAAAGAUUCUGGGAUGGCAAGUUGUUUGCCUUUUCUGAAAAGAGAACAUACAGAACCUGUCCAUCUUUAAGACCUUCAUCCAUGGAAUCUACUAUACAGGAGGAUGCAGUGGGCUGGAGGGGAUGGGCGAAAAUGGGAGCAGGAAGCCUGGCCUGGCUUCUGGUCAUGGCCUCCUAAAACCUUAAACUUCAAGUAGAAAUGUACUCAAGCCCUAUUUAUAAACAAAUACUUUUCCUGCCUCCACCAAACCCCUACAGAACAUCACCUGGAAUUGCCACUCACACUGGGUUGGAGUCAUUGGGCAGCUGUGCCUGUGCGAGAGGUGCUGUGGUCUGGGCAGCCCCUGGAAAAGCACCUUUGCUGCCUGUCAUUGUUGCCUGAAGAAGGCUGGAGUUGCUCUGAGAGCAGUUUGGGUUUGGAGUAUUAUAUUUGGCUUCUAUUUUUAUUAUUUUGGAUCACCAUUCUCCCUAUCCCUUCUUGCCUCCCUCCCUUCUAAACAUGUGUAAUAACUAUACAGAGACUGCUACAAAAUUGUAUAUAGUUUUUGGAUCAAAUAGCAUGAGGGGAGAGGAAACCAUUAAAAGUUGGGGCUCCUACUCUCCUUUGCUUUGUAAAUUCAAAAGUUGGGGGUGGGUAAGAGGGAUAGUUAAAAUGUUUACAAAACUUUAGGCUCCCUCGGAACUUUUGCCAGUGUGGAGGAAAAUAAAAAAGAACUUAAAUAAAAUCUGAUUGUAUUCUAUCUGAGUGCACCUCUUGUACUCACCUUUAUGGAGGCUGAGUUCUGCACUAAACUGUUCCUCUUGGUACCAUGGAAAAGCUCCAAGCACCCAAGACAUGGAGGCAGCCAUGGCUUCUUUCUCUGCCAGACCACGUAGCACUGGCUGGUUCUGUAUUUGAGAAUGUAGAGGUCAAGGCAGAUGUCGGUAAGUUUGACCAAAUAUCUUUUCUCUUUUUGACUCUCCCUUUCUGCUAACAUGUGGAUCAGCUCCUGCCCUCAUACCGCAGACACACCCACUCUGAACACACCCCUCCAGAGCUUGCCCACACCUUCCCAACUAGACUCUGUGUGUGUAUUCAGGAAAAAUGAAAAUAAAUUUUUAAAAAUUGGGAGUGGAAUGGGCAGAUUAGGGGGAACAAAGUCAUUUUGGUCAUGGAACAUCCAUUUGCUUAACCAAGGAGACUUGCUUCUAUCUGAGGAAUUUCCCACUUAGUAGAAAGAAACACUCUUCCCUGGGAAUGUUUGUUUCUGUCUCUCUCAAUGCUACUCUCUUUCAUAUUCUCAUUUGCUCACCCUUUCACUUAGAGCCACCGUUUUCUCAUCCCAUUCUAUGAACUUAUUUCCAAAUUCUCCUAACUAUUCCUGAGUUUUGAAGUAUUUGUUUUGUACCCUCUCUGCUUCCGGUUUUUUGUUUGGUUGGCUUUUUUGGAGAUAGGGUCUUGUGAUGUUGCCCACACUGGUCUCGAGCCCCUGGGCUCAAGUGAUCCUCCCGCCUCAGCCUCCUAAAUAUCUAGGACUACAGGUGUGUGCCACCAUGCCCAGCUCCAGUUUUGUUGGUUGAUUUGUUUAAAUUCAGAGAUUUAAAAACAUCCCAGACAAGACAGUUUGAUUAUGGAGACUGUCCCCAAGCAGAUUGGUGUGCUGGUGGCUGCUGUGCAUAACAGAUUCCCUCCAGAUUGGCUUACAACAGCUACUUCAUUCUGUGGGUCAGGAAUUUGGAUAGGGCUCAGCUGGGUGGUGGUUCUCCUGGGGUAUUCUUUGGUUGUGGUCAGAUGUCUUCCAGGGCAUCAUUCCUAUGAAGGCUUAAUGAAUUAGGCAAGCUGUCCAAGAUGGCUCACUCGUGUAAUGACAGUUGACGUUGGCUGUAGGCUGGGAACUCAGCUGGGUUGAUGACUGGAGGAGCUUAUGUGUGUCGUCUCCGGAAUGGCAGCUUCAGAGGAGUUGAACUUAAGUGGUGAUUGGCUUCCCCCAGAGAACCAGGCAGAAGCUGUGUUACCUUUUUGAGCUCUUAGCUCAGGAGUCACAUAGAGUCACUUCUGUGACACUGUGUUGCAUCAAAGUAGUCACAAACCCACUCAGAUUCAAGAGAAGGGAGCAUGGCCCUCUCCCUGCAACCCCCUCCCCCCCCGCCUUGAUGAAAGGAGUGACAAGGUCACAUUGGAGAAGAGCUUGUGGGGUGGGAGAUAUUAUAGCCAUUUUUGGGAAAUAUCUGCAUAAAAUGAGUUUAUGCAUACAUGAAGGACUUUAUUUUCAUUGGCUUUAAGUUGAGGGUUUUUGUUUUUGUUUUUGUAUUGGAGAUGGGUUCUUACUAUGUUGCCCAGGCUGGUCUCAAACCCCUGGGCUCAAGUGAUCCUGUUGCCUCAGCCUCCCAAGUAGCUGGGACUACAGCUAUGUGCCAGUGCACCCAGCUUGUUUUUUUUAAAUUUUAGGAUAGAUAAUGGUACUUCUGGCUUUAUUUAAAUAAUUUUUUUAGGGAAACCAUUGUAUUUAUACAUGCAUAUAUUUUUAUAUAUACAAAUAUGUAUAUAAAAGUAUAUGUUUUACAUUUUCAAUAUAUAUAUAAUAUAUACAUAUAUGUUAUAUACGUAUAUAUAUUGCACCCUACUUUAAAAUUGACUGAUAACAAAAUUGGUAAUUUUGUAUAAAAUGCCCAACUGUGCAUUAUUAAUAAAAGUAUGUGAAUGACUCUAA